GCCCCGCGAGCGCCGAGACUUGUUGGCCGCGGAGACUGCGACCCUCUUCUCUCAGUCUGCCUUACUACCAUGCCGCUCUACGAGGGCCUGGGGAGCGGCGGGGAGAAGACGGCGGUCGUGAUCGACCUGGGAGAGGCCUUUACCAAGUGUGGAUUUGCUGGAGAAACUGGUCCAAGAUGUAUAAUUCCUAGUGUGAUAAAAAGAGCUGGGAUGCCUAAGCCUGUCAGAGUUGUUCAGUAUAAUAUCAAUACAGAAGAAUUAUAUUCCUACCUAAAGGAAUUCAUCCACAUACUAUAUUUCAGGCAUCUAUUGGUGAAUCCCAGAGACCGCCGAGUUGUGAUUAUCGAAUCGGUAUUAUGUCCUUCUCACUUCAGAGAGACACUCACUCGUGUUCUUUUCAAAUAUUUUGAGGUUCCAUCUGUCUUGCUUGCUCCAAGUCAUCUAAUGGCUCUUCUGACGCUUGGAAUUAAUUCUGCCAUGGUCCUAGAUUGUGGAUAUAGGGAAAGCCUGGUGUUACCCAUAUAUGAAGGAAUCCCAGUUCUAAAUUGUUGGGGAGCACUACCCCUAGGAGGAAAAGCUCUUCACAAAGAGUUGGAAACUCAACUAUUGGAACAAUGUACUGUUGACACAAGUGUUGCUAAAGAACAGAGCCUUCCCUCAGUGAUGGGUUCAGUUCCGGAAGGUGUCUUAGAGGACAUUAAAGGUCUCCUUUUCUUCCUUAAAGCGCGUACUUGCUUUGUAAGUGAUCUGAAGCGAGGACUAAAAAUCCAAGCAGCAAAAUUUAAUAUUGAUGGGAAUAAUGAGCGUCCCUCCCCACCCCCAAAUGUUGACUAUCCAUUAGAUGGAGAGAAGAUUUUACAUAUCCUUGGAUCAAUCAGAGAUUCAGUUGUGGAAAUUCUUUUUGAACAAGAUAAUGAAGAGCAAUCAGUUGCCACUUUAAUAUUGGAUUCCCUUAUACAGUGUCCGAUAGACACCAGGAAGCAACUAGCAGAGAAUUUGGUAGUCAUAGGUGGCACUUCUAUGUUGCCAGGAUUUCUCCACAGAUUGCUUGCAGAAAUAAGGUAUUUGGUAGAAAAACCAAAAUAUAAAAAAGCACUUGGCACUAAGACAUUUCGAAUUCAUACUCCACCUGCAAAAGCUAAUUGUGUGGCCUGGUUGGGAGGGGCUAUUUUUGGAGCAUUACAAGAUAUACUUGGGAGCCGUUCUGUUUCAAAGGAAUAUUAUAAUCAGACGGGCCGUAUACCUGAUUGGUGUUCUCUCAAUAACCCACCUUUGGAAAUGAUGUUUGAUGUCGGGAAAACUCAACCACCUCUGAUGAAGAGAGCAUUUUCCACUGAGAAAUAGAAGUUUGAUUAAAAAUCAACCUUGCUUCAUAUCAAAUAUUUAACCAAUUAUAAGCAAAUUGUACAAAGUAUGUAGGAUGUUUUGUUAUAGAGGACUAUAGUGGAAGUGAAAGCAUUCUGUGUUUACUCUUUGCAUUAAUAUAUAAUUCUUUUGACUUUGUUUCUCUUGUGUAGUGGUAAAAUGGUAGCUGGUGCUUAUUGAGAUUUGCUGUAUUUAUAUCAAUAAAGUAUAGUAAAGCAGUUUGAUUUUGGAAGUUUGUUAUGUGGCUUUUUUUUUUUUUUUUUUUUUGAGACGGAGUCUCGCUCUGUCACUUAGGCUGGAGUGCAGUGGCACAAUCUCUACUCAUUGCAAGCUCCGCCUCCCGGGUUUACGCCAUUCUGUCUCAGCCUCCUGAGUAGCUGGGACUAUAGGCAUACGCCACCCCGCCCGGCUAAUUUUUUGUAUAUUUAGUAGAGACGGGGUUUCACCAUGUUAGCCAGGAUGGUCUCAAUUUCCUGACCUCGUGAUCCACCCUCCUCGGCCUCCCAAAGUGUUGGGAUUACAGGCGUGAACCACUGUACCAGCCUAUGUUGCUUGUCUUUCAAAAAGAACAGUAUUUCUCCACAGUUCACAUAACCUGUUCUGGGCUCAUUAAUUGUGUUUCCAGCAGUUACUCCAUUUAAAGCAUAAAUAGUGUUAACCAUUACCAGUUAUUUCAAAUACUAACAUGGGUCCAUUUAAAAAAAAUAUUUAUUUUGGUACUUGGGUGUCCAUAUUAUAAUAAUGUUGUUUUUCCAGAAAUAUAUUUGAUCUUUGGACUGAGAAUGUUUGGUAACAUAGUCAAGCAUUUGUUAAGCCAAGUGUGGAAAUGUUCACUUUUUAACUUUACAGUUUUUUUAAUGAGCAAUUCUACAUUUCUAAGAAAAAAGAUACUUCAUUUUUAUAUAAGGUUACAACUGCUUUAUAAAAAUGUAUUCACAAUGUCAUUAAUCUUUGCGUUUGUGCUUUAUAUCUUCUCAGGGCAGAGGUUCUUGAAAUAUGUACUCAAUCAUUUAACUUUUAUUUUAUUUUUUCAUUUGUUUUUAAUGAACUACCUCUUGUUGAAA